GCACUUCUCCCUGCUGCCACCUUGUGAAGAAAGUGCCUUGCUUCCCCUUUGCCUACCACCAUGAUAGUAAGUUUCCUGAGGCCUCCUGAGCCAUGCUGAACUACCAAUUUUCUUUGCGUAUGCCCUUGGAGUUAUUAGCUCAAAGAAUAGAUUUCUCUUGGCCCACCUGGAAGCCUUCUCUUUUCCUAACUGAUGACUUUGGAUUAUACAACUUUACCUACUGUUAAAAGUACACAGAUGAAAAGAGUAAAGGGUAUUUGACUGACGAGUGAACAUGAGCUCAAAGCCCGACAAGAUAUUCUGCCUCAAGAGAAGAUCAAAACUCCUGUAACCUCUGUGAGGCUAUCCAAAUCCCAGCAGGGAACAGGUAUCUUCCAUUUAACUCUAAACCUGACUUUGCCUUUUUUACUUAAACAUUAAUUUUCCUAAAACAACCAAGCAUUUUUGUAUUGUCAGAGCUCUUUCAACUGCAAGGGAUAAACCUUGAUUUCACUAAAUAGAGAAAGAAGACAAGGAGGAUAAUGGCCUUAGGCACAAUUGGACCCGAGGGCUCUAACGAGGUCAGAAGACCAGUGUCUCAUUUUUCUUGGCAUUGCUGGGCUUUGUUUACUUCUAGACUGCCUUCAUUUUCAGUGUUGCUUUUGUUAUAUGAUGCCCCCCAACCCUUACCCAGAAACUCCACAUUUAGAGCCAAACAGGUUAAAAAUUUCAAAGGAAAGUUGGCUCCCCUAUGUCUCUAUUGGGGAAAAAAAAAAUCCUGAGACUAUCUCUGUUAAUCUAGUCUGUGUCACGUGACUCUUCUGAUGGGCCCGACCUGAGUCACAUGCCCCUACCUUAAGUCAGGGGGUGGAGCUAGCCCCACCAAAUCAUCUGUCCUGGAAGGAGAGUAUAGGUGAGUCCUCAGAGGAGAGUCAAAGGUGCUCUUAACAGCAGAAGAAAGAAUUGAUGCUGGACAGGUGUUCCGACUAGGUGCUCUGUCUCCGUAGCUGUCAUAAUCCUUUGUCUUCUUUCUUCAGUAGUGUGUCUGCUUUUCCUCUAUGCCUCGUGUCUCCCACGUACCUCAUUGUGUAGCAUUAAUCAGUGUUACUCUCAUCAUCCUUAUUGUACAGGCCUGGAUACUCUGCUUUAUUGUGAGUCCUUGAGAGCGGGAGCCGCGGCUCAUUUAGUUCACCAUCCCCACUGAUUAGCAUAAUUCCUGGCACAUACAUAGUAGAUAAUCUAAUGAGUUUUCCAAAAAGGAAGAAAUUGAUGAUCCCCCUGGAAAUCAAGUCCCUGAAUGGGUGACACCGUUCAAAGGUAUGAACAUGGUCUUAAGGCUCAAGUGAAAACUCCAUGAUGAACAGUGACGGCUGUCACAUAAGGAAGAUGCCUGGAAGCAAACUGAAGAAUGUGCCAUUAUGAGUCUGCACUGCUGGGUUCAAAACAAAACAAGUAGAAAGAAGCCACCUAAUUUUGGCCUUGUCAACCCUUCAUGAGAUGUAUGACAACAGGCAAAUGGAUACAAUUUUGACUUAAACAUGAAUACAGUAAUUUGAAAUCCUGCCAGGAUUUCAUUUUAACCUCUGUAGAUGACAAGUAGAGGACAAAUGUAAUUCUCUCUCACUGCUCUUCUGGAAGAAUUGUCUUGGCACCUUUCUUUCUUCCUAAUUCCCUUCUCCAUCCUUUUCUUCCAUCCUUCCCACCUCUCUUGGCUCUUCCCUUCUAUCUCUCUCCAUCUCUCCUCAUAUUUUUCUACUGCUCCCCUCUGCUUUUGCCCUUUGCAGGAAUCACGGCUUUUGAUUUACAGGGCUCAUUUAAAUUCUGCCUAUGUGACCUUGGGCAAGUUGCUUCAUCUUUUGGAGCUUACUCUCCUCAUCUGUAACACUGGAAUAUUAAUAUGCAUUACUAAUAUUCCAGUCAGGCUCAAUGAUAUUAUGUAUGUAAAAUGCUCAGCACAGACUAGAGGGAGUGCAUUUGAAGAGAAGUAGAAGAAAAUUGUAUUUGCUGUGGGGUAGUGGGGAUUGUAAACAAGAGACUGUGUUAGUUCUAAGUUCUCCCUGUCUCAAACCAGCCAGAGUCCAAAGUGCCUCAUCUGUUGGAUGACAGUGCUUGGAAGCCCUGCCAAUGAAAUGGCCACUGCAGAGUGUUUGUCUCCUAAUGGUAAAGUGUGGUGAUUAAGUCCCUUACAUUUAAAGUCAGAUUACCAGGGUUCAAACUUUUGCUCAGCAGUGGCAUGGCCACAGGUAAGAUCAUUCCUUCAUUCACUUAUUUAGAACACGUUCUCUGUGUGAGUCAGUAGGGGUUUGUGUCACAACUAUGAACAAGGCCAACCAGGUCUUGCCCUCCUGGAGCUUAUUUUCUAUUGAGAGAAAACAAGACAGACAAGUAAACAAAUAUACUUGUAAAUAAAAUAAUUUUAGAUCAGGAUAAGACAAUCAGACAAAGCAAGGGAGUAGAGAAUCAUGGGGAAAAGACAGCAGCUUCUUUGAGACUGAUGUGUACAAUGAGGAGGUGACUUCAAGGGAGUGAGGGUGACUGGUCAGAAGGGACAGCGUUGCAGGCAGAGGGAAGAAUAAGUACAAAGGAUGCAUGUGGAUGAAGCUAUCCUGAAGUCCAGGUUAACUUGUUUCGAUUUUAUCUGAUAAACUCUGGGGAGCCUCUGAAGGGCUUUAAGCAGAGAUGUGACAUGACCUGAGCAGCACUGGGGAGAGACAGCCCUCAGGCCCUCAUUCAUUCCUUUGGGGAUAACAAGCUCUUUCCAGAGAGAAGGGAAUUCCCAGGGCACUGCCCAAUACAAGGUAAGAAUUCAAGGUAAAUUGCUGAGUAUGGAUGGUGUCGUUCUUGAUGGUGGCGGGGCAAAAGCAGAGACGUCAAAGCCAGCCAGUUAAUGAAAUAAGAACAAAUCUUUGACAGUUCCAUUGAGCUGAGCUUGAAUCAGGCGUUCCUGAUGUGGCUGAAUCUGGUUGUGUGCACGUCUGGUGUUCAGUGGAGUGAAAUCAGAAGGUGUCAGGAUUCGCAACUCCUAAAACAGCUUGGUUUUAUCAAAAUCAGGACCUCUUUGAACCUUCCUUUUCUCCACAAUGCAGAUAAUAAUACGAUCUAUCUCACAAAGUAGUGAGGAUGAAACAAGGCAAUGAAUGUAAAGAGUUUAGACAGGGCUAGCAUCUGGCACAUAGAGCUCAGUAAGUGUUGCCAGCAAUUAUUAUGAUUGUUUAUUACCGAUUAUUAUCUCAACACAUACCUGCCCCAUCUUUGUUGAAUUCUGUCAUAUAGGCAUGGCCGGUGAUCCUAUAAUUGCCACAUUCCUCUCCUCUUCCCAGCCCCUACCUCUACUCUCCUCAGGCUCCUCGUUUUUCUCCAGAUUCCACCAGGGGACCCAGGAACAGACAUUUACAGUGCAGAAAUAAUCACAGUAGCUGCCAUUCAUCAAGCUAUCUCCAUAGGCAGAGCUGGACCAAGGUCUUUUGUACAUUAUCUCAAUUAUGAGAACAAUCCUAAUAUAUUUGUUUCCUAUCUCCACUGUAGAGGUGAGAAAAUUGAGGCUCAAAAGGGUAGGUGACCACUACAGGGUCACUCAGUCAGCAAGAGGCAGAGCUGGGAUUCAGACUCACAUCCAUCUGACCCACAGGUUCCCUAAAAUGAAACAAAAUUAAAGCAUCCAUUUAGUGCCCCCCCGCCACAAAGCACCAUUGACUAUGAAAUGGUCAUAGUCAAUAUAACAUAUAACACAUAACACAUAAGUGUUAUAUAAGGAAAGGACACCCUAUUCAACAAAUGGUGCUGGGAUAAUUGGCAUAUAACACAUAAGUAAGUUAGGAGGGCAUAGUGAGUGAUCAGUGCAAGGAGAGCUUGAGAGUCUCAAAGAGCCUCCUGGAGUCAACCCAGAAUCCAAAAAUGUCCUCUAAUUUCAAAGGAGCCUUUGCCCCCCACAGGCCAGUGGCAGCACAAAGAGAUGGUAUUACUUUGACGGUGGCCAUGUGGUUGUGAGGAAGCCCCCGACCCCUUUCCGGCCUCUUUGUCUUCUUUAGGGCUCCAUCUGUGGCCCUGCUCACACAGCCCUGCUGGUCUUGACUCUGAGGUGAAGGAGUAAACAUCUUGGGGCUCUUUAUUAGUUUAUUUCAGAAGAUGGAGCCUGUUUGCCCCUGGGGCCCAUCCCUCUUUUAUGGCCUCCAGGCUUUCUUGACAAAUUCUAGUGACUGGAGAGAAAACCGCUUUCUACAGCAGAUCAUUAAAACACCACCAUAAACCCAGGGCCAUAAAAUAUUAUUUGCUGGGCAUAAAAGGGGGGUAGAUUUUCCCAGAAUGACAACCCAGGCCCUGCUUUCCCCUGCUGGGAAAGGCGGCACAGGGAUGCAGUCGUUCAUAAAUUCCUUAUCUUGCACUCUGCUUUGUGAAUAAUCCGGUUGGGAGAGCAGCCAAAAAUAUUGAUUUAUUUGUUCCACAGAUUCAGAAGCAUUUUUAAUGAGCAGAGUGUGGUGAUGCCUUGCCAGUAUAUCUUCGGAUGACUCAAUCUGAGGCACACACCCAAAUGCACACACGGUUUGCAAGGGGAAACAUGAAGUUCCACAAACUGGAGGUCUGUCGAACAUGAACCCUCACAGAUGGAGAGGCAUUGGUUUCUCUCCUUCCAACUGUCUGCUCAUUUCCCAGCCAAACCAAUCAACACCAUCAUGGGACUGGUGCUUACAACUGAGCCUGGCUUUCUAAGGCAGUCCCCACCCCUACCCACUAUUGAAGGGUCAAAAGGGAUUUCAAGUUGGUUCUCCUUAACACCGUCCUCUGAAAUAAUUCUUUCAUCCAUUCGCCCAUUCGUGUGGUUGUUACUUCUAAGCACCUACUAAGUGCCAGGCAUUGUUCUGAGGACUGGGGUUCCAGCCAUGAAAACCGCAGAUGAGGUCCUGCUGACAUGAAGCUUAUUGCUCCUGGGGCAUAAUCUCAGCACACUAAUUAUUAAUAUUAUCAGAUAAAACAACUCUUUAUCUGAAGUCCUUGGGACUAGACGGUUUUGUUGGAAAUUUUGGGAAAAUAAAAUGGGGCAUAUUGCUAUUAAUUUGCAAGCAGCCCAGUGAGGUCUGGGGAAAUACCCAGUAACCAAAUGCAUUUGUAUUCAUUCAGUGAAGAGUAUUCCUAGCAAGUGGAAUAAAUCAAGAUUAUGUCUUGUCAUGUGAGGUCCAGUUUUACCACCACAGGAGUUUGAAAACCUCUGUUUUCAGAGCUGCUUUUUUUCUAGAAGAGCAGGCAUUGAGUGCCAGGUAAGGGCCUGACCCAUGCUAAGAGCAUUCCUAGAUAUCGUGUUUCAUUCUCAGUACUGCCCUGAUUUUCAAGCUCAUCUCAUUUCAUUCUCAAUGCAUUUCUGCAAGGUAGAUCAUGAAAUUUCUGCUUGCUGCUGUUGUUGCUGUUGUUGUGUGUAAGAGGGUUCUGAAGUGCUGGCUGAGAGGCUAGACAAGGUGUGACAGCUGGAAAGUGGCAGGGCAGGGACUGGAACUCCAGAUUCCACAGCUGGCACUCUUAACCACUAACCAACACCGACUUCCACUAGAGGAAAGACUGCAGAACAGGAAAUAGCACUGUUUGGGCUGUGUCUAUACAAGCAAAGGCAAUUGGAGAGAAGCAGGUGAUUAUCCAGAUAACUCAGAAAAUAGCCAUUAAAAAAUAAAGGUUUGUGGUUGGGUAGCCAGUAUUUCUAGACUGGCUGUAUGUGUGGAGGAAAUGCCCAGGUUAACGGCCCUUUUCUUCAUAGAAUAGGAUCCUCUACACGAACUGCCUUGGACUCUGGGACACUGGGAUGCUAGUUUCUCCAUUCUUCGGGAGCGCCCUUUGGCAGCCCCUUUCAUAGUCAGCUCAUAUCCUGCCACUUCUUGGAGCUGCUGCACGUAAGAAGUCCAUUGGAAUAUUAAGCCCAGGAGUUGCUUUGGGGAUGGCUGGAAGUGCAAUGUCUUCCAAGUUCUUCCUAGUGGCUUUGGCCAUAUUUUUCUCCUUCGCCCAGGUUGUAAUUGAAGCCAAUUCUUGGUGGUCGCUAGGUAUGAAUAACCCUGUUCAGAUGUCAGAAGUAUAUAUUAUAGGAGCACAGCCUCUCUGCAGCCAACUGGCAGGACUUUCUCAAGGACAGAAGAAACUGUGCCACUUGUAUCAGGACCACAUGCAGUACAUCGGAGAAGGCGCGAAGACAGGCAUCAAAGAAUGCCAGUAUCAAUUCCGACAUCGAAGGUGGAACUGCAGCACUGUGGAUAACACCUCUGUUUUUGGCAGGGUGAUGCAGAUAGGCAGCCGCGAGACGGCCUUCACAUACGCGGUGAGCGCAGCAGGGGUGGUGAACGCCAUGAGCCGGGCGUGCCGCGAGGGCGAGCUGUCCACCUGCGGCUGCAGCCGCGCCGCGCGCCCCAAGGACCUGCCGCGGGACUGGCUCUGGGGCGGCUGCGGCGACAACAUCGACUAUGGCUACCGCUUUGCCAAGGAGUUCGUGGACGCCCGCGAGCGGGAGCGCAUCCACGCCAAGGGCUCCUACGAGAGUGCUCGCAUCCUCAUGAACCUGCACAACAACGAGGCCGGCCGCAGGACGGUGUACAACCUGGCUGAUGUGGCCUGCAAGUGCCAUGGGGUGUCCGGCUCAUGUAGCCUGAAGACAUGCUGGCUGCAGCUGGCAGACUUCCGCAAGGUGGGUGAUGCCCUGAAGGAGAAGUACGACAGCGCGGCGGCCAUGCGGCUCAACAGCCGGGGCAAGUUGGUACAGGUCAACAGCCGCUUCAACUCGCCCACCACACAAGACCUGGUCUACAUCGACCCCAGCCCUGACUACUGCGUGCGCAAUGAGAGCACCGGCUCGCUGGGCACGCAGGGCCGCCUGUGCAACAAGACGUCGGAGGGCAUGGAUGGCUGCGAGCUCAUGUGCUGCGGCCGUGGCUACGACCAGUUCAAGACCGUGCAGACGGAGCGCUGCCACUGCAAGUUCCACUGGUGCUGCUACGUCAAGUGCAAGAAGUGCACGGAGAUCGUGGACCAGUUUGUGUGCAAGUAGUGGGUGCCACCCAGCACUCAGCCCCGCUCCCAGGACCCGCUUAUUUAUAGAAAGUACAGUGAUUCUGGUUUUUGGUUUUUAGAAAUAUUUUUUAUUUUUCCCCAAGAAUUGCAACCGGAACCAUUUUUUUUCCUGUUACCAUCUAAGAACUCUGUGGUUUAUUAUUAAUAUUAUAAUUAUUAUUUGGCAAUAAUGGGGGUGGGAACCAAGAAAAAUAUUUAUUUUGUGGAUCUUUGAAAAGGUAAUACAAGACUUCUUUUGAUAGUAUAGAAUGAAGGGGAAAUAACACAUACCCUAACUUAGCUGUGUGGACAUGGUACACAUCCAGAAGGUAAAGAAAUACAUUUUCUUUUUCUCAAAUAUGCCAUCAUAUGGGAUGGGUAGGUUCCAGUUGAAAGAGGGUGGUAGAAAUCUAUUCACAAUUCAGCUUCUAUGACCAAAAUGAGUUGUAAAUUCUCUGGUGCAAGAUAAAAGGUCUUGGGAAAACAAAACAAAACAAAACAAACCUCCCUUCCCCAGCAGGGCUGCUAGCUUGCUUUCUGCAUUUUCAAAAUGAUAAUUUACAAUGGAAGGACAAGAAUGUCAUAUUCUCAAGGAAAAAAGGUAUAUCACAUGUCUCAUUCUCCUCAAAUAUUCCAUUUGCAGACAGACCGUCAUAUUCUAAUAGCUCAUGAAAUUUGGGCAGCAGGGAGGAAAGUCCCCAGAAAUUAAAAAAUUUAAAACUCUUAUGUCAAGAUGUUGAUUUGAAGCUGUUAUAAGAAUUAGGAUUCCAGAUUGUAAAAAGAUCCCCAAAUGAUUCUGGACACUAGAUUUUUUUGUUUGGGGAGGUUGGCUUGAACAUAAAUGAAAAUAUCCUGUUAUUUUCUUAGGGAUACUUGGUUAGUAAAUUAUAAUAGUAAAAAUAAUACAUGAAUCCCAUUCACAGGUUCUCAGCCCAAGCAACAAGGUAAUUGCGUGCCAUUCAGCACUGCACCAGAGCAGACAACCUAUUUGAGGAAAAACAGUGAAAUCCACCUUCCUCUUCACACUGAGCCCUCUCUGAUUCCUCCGUGUUGUGAUGUGAUGCUGGCCACGUUUCCAAACGGCAGCUCCACUGGGUCCCCUUUGGUUGUAGGACAGGAAAUGAAACAUUAGGAGCUCUGCUUGGAAAACAGUUCACUACUUAGGGAUUUUUGUUUCCUAAAACUUUUAUUUUGAGGAGCAGUAGUUUUCUAUGUUUUAAUGACAGAACUUGGCUAAUGGAAUUCACAGAGGUGUUGCAGCGUAUCACUGUUAUGAUCCUGUGUUUAGAUUAUCCACUCAUGCUUCUCCUAUUGUACUGCAGGUGUACCUUAAAACUGUUCCCAGUGUACUUGAACAGUUGCAUUUAUAAGGGGGGAAAUGUGGUUUAAUGGUGCCUGAUAUCUCAAAGUCUUUUGUACAUAACAUAUAUAUAUAUAUACAUAUAUAUAAAUAUAAAUAUAAAUAUAUCUCAUUGCAGCCAGUGAUUUAGAUUUACAGUUUACUCUGGGGUUAUUUCUCUGUCUAGAGCAUUGUUGUCCUUCACUGCAGUCCAGUUGGGAUUAUUCCAAAAGUUUUUUGAGUCUUGAGCUUGGGCUGUGGCCCUGCUGUGAUCAUACCUUGAGCACGACGAAGCAACCUUGUUUCUGAGGAAGCUUGAGUUCUGACUCACUGAAAUGCGUGUUGGGUUGAAGAUAUCUUUUUUCUUUUCUGCCUCACCCCUUUGUCUCCAACCUCCAUUUCUGUUCACUUUGUGGAGAGGGCAUUACUUGUUCGUUAUAGACAUGGACGUUAAGAGAUAUUCAAAACUCAGAAGCAUCAGCAAUGUUUCUCUUUUCUUAGUUCAUUCUGCAGAAUGGAAACCCAUGCCUAUUAGAAAUGACAGUACUUAUUAAUUGAGUCCCUAAGGAAUAUUCAGCCCACUACAUAGAUAGCUUUUUUUUUUUUUUUUUUAAUAAGGACACCUCUUUCCAAACAGUGCCAUCAAAUAUGUUCUUAUCUCAGACUUACGUUGUUUUAAAAGUUUGGAAAGAUACACAUCUUUCAUACCCCCCUUAGGCAGGUUGGCUUUCAUAUCACCUCAGCCAACUGUGGCUCUUAAUUUAUUGCAUAAUGAUAUUCACAUCCCCUCAGUUGCAGUGAAUUGUGAGCAAAAGAUCUUGAAAGCAAAAAGCACUAAUUAGUUUAAAAUGUCACUUUUUUGGUUUUUAUUAUACAAAAACCAUGAAGUACUUUUUUUAUUUGCUAAAUCAGAUUGUUCCUUUUUAGUGACUCAUGUUUAUGAAGAGAGUUGAGUUUAACAAUCCUAGCUUUUAAAAGAAACUAUUUAAUGUAAAAUAUUCUACAUGUCAUUCAGAUAUUAUGUAUAUCUUCUAGCCUUUAUUCUGUACUUUUAAUGUACAUAUUUCUGUCUUGCGUGAUUUGUAUAUUUCACUGGUUUAAAAAACAAACAUCGAAAGGCUUAUGCCAAAUGGAAGAUAGAAUAUAAAAUAAAACGUUACUUGUAUAUUGGUAAGUGGUUUCAAUUGUCCUUCAGAUAAUUCAUGUGGAGAUUUUUGGAGAAACCAUGACGGAUAGUUUAGGAUGACUACAUGUCAAAGUAAUAAAAGAGUGGUGAAUUUUACCAAAACCAAGCUAUUUGGAAGCUUCAAAAGGUUUCUAUAUGUAAUGGAACAAAAGGGGAAUUCUCUUUUCCUAUAUAUGUUCCUUACAAAAAAAAAAAAAAAAGAAAUCAAGCAGAUGGCUUAAAGCUGGUUAUAGGAUUGCUCACAUUCUUUUAGCAUUAUGCAUGUAACUUAAUUGUUUUAGAGCGUGUUGCUGUUGUAACAUCCCAGAGAAGAAUGAAAAGGCACAUGCUUUUAUCCGUGACCAGAUUUUUAGUCCAAAAAAAUGUAUUUUUUUGUGUGUUUACCACUGCAACUAUUGCACCUCUCUAUUUGAAUUUACUGUGGACCAUGUGUGGUGUCUCUAUGCCCUUUGAAAGCAGUUUUUAUAAAAAGAAAGCCCGGGUCUGCAGAGAAUGAAAACUGGUUGGAAACUAAAGGUUCAUUGUGUUAAGUGCAAUUAAUACAAGUUAUUGUGCUUUUCAAAAAUGUACACGGAAAUCUGGACAGUGCUCCACAGAUUGAUACAUUAGCCUUUGCUUUUUCUCUUUCCGGAUAACCUUGUAACAUAUUGAAACCUUUUAAGGAUGCCAAGAAUGCAUUAUUCCACAAAAAAACAGCAGACCAACAUAUAGAGUGUUUAAAAUAGCAUUUCUGGGCAAAUUCAAACUCUUGUGGUUCUAGGACUCACAUCUGUUUCAGUUUUUCCUCAGUUGUAUAUUGACCAGUGUUCUUUAUUGCAAAAACAUAUACCCGAUUUAGCAGUGUCAGCGUAUUUUUUCUUCUCAUCCUGGAGCGUAUUCAAGAUCUUCCCAAUACAAGAAAAUUAAUAAAAAAUUUAUAUAUAGGCAGCAGCAAAAGAGCCAUGUUCAAAAUAGUCAUUAUGGGCUCAAAUAGAAAGAAGACUUUUAAGUUUUAAUCCAGUUUAUCUGUUGAGUUCUGUGAGCUACUGACCUCCUGAGACUGGCACUGUGUAAGUUUUAGUUGCCUACCCUAGCUCUUUUCUCGUACAAUUUUGCCAAUACCAAGUUUCAAUUUGUUUUUACAAAACAUUAUUCAAGCCACUAGAAUUAUCAAAUAUGACGCUAUAGCAGAGUAAAUACUCUGAAUAAGAGACCGGUACUAGCUAACUCCAAGAGAUCGUUAGCAGCAUCAGUCCACAAACACUUAGUGGCCCACAAUAUAUAGAGAGAUAGAAAAGGUAGUUAUAACUUGAAGCAUGUAUUUAAUGCAAAUAGGCACGAAGGCACAGGUCUAAAAUACUACAUUGUCACUGUAAGCUAUACUUUUAAAAUAUUUAUUUUUUUUAAAGUAUUUUCUAGUCUUUUCUCUCUCUGUGGAAUGGUGAAAGAGAGAUGCCGUGUUUUGAAAGUAAGAUGAUGAAAUGAAUUUUUAAUUCAAGAAACAUUCAGAAACAUAGGAAUUAAAACUUAGAGAAAUGAUCUAAUUUCCCUGUUCACACAAACUUUACACUUUAAUCUGAUGAUUGGAUAUUUUAUUUUAGUGAAACAUCAUCUUGUUAGCUAACUUUAAAAAAUGGAUGUAGAAUGAUUAAAGGUUGGUAUGAUUUUUUUUUAAUGUAUCAGUUUGAACCUAGAAUAUUGAAUUAAAAUGCUGUCUCAGUAUUUUAAAAGCAAAAAAGGAAUGGAGGAAAAUUGCAUCUUAGACCAUUUUUAUAUGCAGUGUACAAUUUGCUGGGCUAGAAAUGAGAUAAAGAUUAUUUAUUUUUGUUCAUAUCUUGUACUUUUCUAUUAAAAUCAUUUUAUGAAAUCCA